GCAUUCUCUUCUCUGCUCUGCAAAUUCCAGCUUGUACUUAAAUACUUCCUGCGAAGUUUUGACUGAGACGCUGCAACAAUUCCCGAGCUGUUUCAUCGUGGCACCUUCCUGGUGGCAGGUGGAUUAGCACAUUGUCUGCAACCCAGGAGGACUUGGAGGAAAGUCCCAGCUCUGCUGAUUCUAGCUGAGUAACCUUGGCAAAGGUCACCUCACUUCUCUCUGAGUCUUAUUUUCUCAUCUGUAAAAUGAGGAGGAGGAGGAGGAUCAUCCAAACAUCACGGGACUUCGUUAAAUCAGUGCUUCGGGGCACUUAGCACAGCGCCUGGCGCAAGGUUCUUUGUGAACUUCCCCUCGGCCAAGCAGUACUUCAGCCAGUUCAAGCACAUGGAGGAUCCCCUGGAGAUGGAGCGGAGCCCCCAGCUGCGGAAGCACGCCUGCCGAGUCAUGGGGGCCCUCAACACUGUCGUGGAGAACCUGCAUGACCCCGACAAGGUGUCCUCUGUGCUCGCCCUUGUGGGGAAAGCCCACGCCCUCAAGCACAAGGUGGAACCGGUGUACUUCAAGAUCCUCUCUGGGGUCAUUCUGGAGGUGGUCGCCGAGGAAUUUGCCAGUGACUUCCCACCUGAGACGCAGAGAGCCUGGGCCAAGCUGCGUGGCCUCAUCUACAGCCACGUGACCGCUGCCUACAAGGAAGUGGGCUGGGUGCAGCAGGUCCCCAACGCCACCACGCACAGCUCCUGGAGGAGGUCCCCUGAGGGCAGCUGGGGACGCCAGGCCUCCUGCCCUUCCUGCUGCUGACCACACUGGCCCCGGGCUGGCUCCUGCUCCCCUCCCCCCUCUCCCGUCAGCACCACCCCAAGAGAGUGGAGUCCUCGGGAACUGCUGGCUGGAGCCAAGCCAACUCCAGAUGUGCACAGCUGGGCCCUGGCCUGCCUGAGACCUGGGAGUCAAUGGGAAACAAGCAGAUGUUGGCCCACCAGAGGAGGGCACUGGCAGGGCGUGGAGAGCAGUGGUUGCCCCCUCACCCCCCACCAGCUGUCACCCAGAGGGUCCAGGGAAAAGACAGGGGAAGAGGAGGGGAGGGGGCUUGCCUGCCCUCCCACCCCUCUCCCCACGCAGGCUCUGCUGCCAAAGAUGAGUUUGUUUACAGCCAGGACACAAGACUUCCUGCUUCCAGAGAAAAGGGCUUUUUUACAAGGGCCAAGAGAGACUGGAAAGAGAGCUGGCUGGGCGCGAGCCCCAGUGAAUCAGAAACACAUGGCCCAAGUUCCCCAGCACGCUGCCCGUCCUGCCCUCCCCACCCUGCCCUAGGGACUAAGAUCUCUCCAAACCCCAAACAUUUUGAAACGGCCGAAGUCUCCUCCUCCGCCCACUUCUGCUCCUUGUGGACUGAAUGGAGAUGGGCUACCGUGGAAACUGGCACCCCAUGGGGGUUACUCCCAGCUGUCAAGUGGUGGGGUGGUCCCCUCAUCCCUUUACACCCUCUAGCCCACCCCUAGUGUCCCUGGCCUGAGCCUGCAGAGCCUCCCUGCUGCCAGGGUCCCCAUGGGCUCGAGGGUAGGAUGGAGUUACAGAGUAGAGUCCUAGAAGGCCCUCGCCCAACUUCUCUUAUCAGGGAAGCAGGGGUGGGCCAGGCGCCACUGUUUAUUGAGCCGUCUCUGCUCCAGGGUGUGCGCCUUUGCGUGGGUGGGGGGUGGGGGGGGGGCGCAAUGACUGCAGGGGGCGCUGUGUGUACCGAGAAUACGAGAAUACAGAUGGGUGGCCCGAGGAGGGACGAGACAGGCCGGACAGAAUGCGCCACGUUUCAGAAUUAAUGGAAAAAGAGCUCACAUUGGUAUCGUGCUUUGCAGUUUGUGAAACACUUUUUUACCCAGUUUAUGUCACAAGACAGACAUUAUUCACAUUUUAGAGAAAAAGAUCCGGAGCUCCCAUGGGCCAGUAGACUUGCCUGAGAUCACACAGCACGUUCGUAGCAGGACGGAGACUAGAACUUGGGUCUCACGGUUGCUUUCAACUGCACUGUGCCGGAUCUCUUGGCAGGAAGUGAGCCUCGCCAGCCCCAGGUCCUCCCCCUUUCCCCCGAGGGUCCUUCCCUGCCUCUGGUAACGUUUGUCCUUCCCUUCCUAUCUCGU